GGACCUGGACUGGGCUGAGCAUGGAGUGAGGAGGACGAGAGCAGAGAGACCCCCGGGACUUCAUCAGGCCUGGCAGCUGACUGCAUGUGGGGUGAAAAAAGGAAGCCACAGGACAGCGCACAAGGGUAUGGUGUGGAGAUGGAGGUGGAGAUGGCACAGCAGGCCACACAGAGAAGAAACCUACAGGGAGGUAGCUGGGUUUGAGGUGCUUGAGGGGCAGAUGGGUGGUCUGAUGGGCAGGUAGACAGAAGGGUCUGCAGCCGGGGAGGAGACUGAGAUACAUGAGACCAUCCAGGGAGAGGGGACCCAGGGGGAAGAGCAAAGGACCGGAUCCUGGGAACUGGACAGUUGUGAUUUGGCCAAGACAGAAAAGCCUGUGAAAGAGACCAAAAAAACCCAAGUGCAGUGUGAGGAGAGGCCCGCAGAGAAGAGUCUUGGAAGCUGAGGGGAGGUGACCUCAGCAGCACAGUGGACAGCGGUGCCAGUGACUUGGGAAGGUCAGAAAACAGAAGAUGGAAAGUGGGUUUGGAAACCAGGGAGACCUGGGGAGAGCAGGUUGGCCGCAGCGGCAGGAGCUGGAAUGGGAGGGGGUGCAUGAGGCUGAGUGUGGCGCAUCCUCCUCGGGGCUGAGAUGGAUUUUACUUGUCUUGGGUUCCCCACGGCUGUCACAGGGCAGUGUCUCAGUUCAUUCGUCUUUUUCCUUCAGGAAGUCUGGGUGUAAAGGGAUGGAGAGAGGUGAGGUGUGUGCAGUAAGAGGAUUUCUCAAGGAUGGGACAGGAAGGCCUUGGAGCUUUGGCUUCCUCCUGUGAACUUGUGGGGUGGGGAGCCUGGUGCACCAACCUGAGGGACUUGAGGGAGUAGUAUCAGGAUGUGGGAUUGAGCCCUGGACCUUUUUUCUAGAAAGAGGAAAAAAAUGAAGGGAGGAGGAGGAGGAAGCUGGGGAGAUCACACCUUUGAUUUUCUUGUUCCUGGAAAGUGAAAGGAAGUUCACCUGCUAUGAGUGAGAAGGUGGACACACUGGGUGGGGAUGAGGUGAGUGACAUGAGCUUAGGAAAGUUGCUGAGGUAAUUGGUUGAGAGAGGUGUUCAAAUAAAAAUAACGCAAUUGGCAAAAACUGUUACUAAGACUUUGUAGAGGCACCAAUCAGUGACAUGGCAGCAUUUUCUUUCACAGUAAUCAACUGCCAGAUUGCAGACAGCCCUGAUGCCAGCCUAAGGAGUGUGGGUUUCUCCUCCAGGCCCGCAGGUCCCCAACCUCACUCCUCUGAAGACUCUUCUGGAGAUCCUCUGUGAUGCACAGAUCUCCAGACUCAGUGCCCCCAGACUCAGAUUCCCUGGGUGGGGAGGUCUGGGGAUCUCUGCUUGUAAUCAGCUCCCUAGAGGUUCCCAUGUAGCCAGAUAAGUAUUGUCAGAACACUGAAGAUUUUUGAAAAAUGAAAAAGAGAAGGUUGGAGAUGUGUCUUCAGAAGACUACUAAGGGUGCUGGCUAGAGGAGGGACCAGAGGCAGGGAGAUGAGGUAGGAAACUGCUAUUAUUUGUCAGGGAAAUUGCAAUCAAGGCAUGAGUUAGAACAGGGAAAACACAGAGGCAAGGGAGAGGUGGAAGGGGGAGGAAAGAAGUAGUGACAAUUCCAGGGUGGAUGUCCACCCAAAUCUAGAAGUAAUUGAGCAAAUGUUUUCUGGGCAUUAGAGAAGGCAACUAGAACAAACAGGAAUCCUUGCCUUGGUGAAAUGUAUUUGAACUGGGUCAGAAAUGAGGCCAUUGGGUAUCAGGCCUUAACUCCAGCGCACCCUGGAGGUCACUGAUGUGGCUCCAGGCUGACCUGCUCCUGUCAAAGAAUAUUGAGCAAGAUGCCUCUCGUGGAAUGUUCUGGGACCUUAAAACAGAUACCCAAGUAUUCCCCCUGAUUUCAUGGUUCCCAGAAGCUCUAUGGGGAAGAAAUUGUAGGUAAUUCACAACUGAGAUUUAGACAUAAGUUGAAUAGUGUAAUGGACAUUGAGUUAACCGAGGUAAUGAAGUAGUGAGACACAGGUGCCCCUGAAAUAAACUCACAUUGAGGGAAGAGGCUGACAAUGUGGAUCAGUCUGAAAACAAGGCAAAAAUACAAUAGGGAGUAAGGGUUGUGUGUCAGUUCAAGACUGUACUUUUACCUGGCCCAGCGCCAUGUUAGGGUAUUUGUGUUCUCCAGGAAGUAGAAAGGAAAGAACUGAGUGAUUAGGGACCUAGAAGACUAAUUUGAGACAUUCCUCUUGAUGAGCUGUUCUCUAGGGUAGUCCUCUGAAAGAGCUGUUCUCUAGUGGAUCUCCCUGAAUGAACUGUUCUCUAGGAGCACUUGACCCUUUUCUGUGUUUGUUUUUUGUUUUGUGUUUGUGUUUGUUUUUGAGACAGGUUCUCACUUUGUCUCCCAGGCUGGAGUGCUGUGGCACCAUCAUGGCUCACUGCAGCCUCAACCUCCUGGGCUCAAGUGAUCCUCCUGCCUCAGCCUCCCAUGUAGCUAGAACUACAGAUACACGUACCACCAUGUCUGGCUAAUUUAUUUUUCUUUUUAGAGAUGGGUUCUCACUAUGUUGCCCAGGCCGGUCUCAAAACCCUGGGCUCAAGUGAUCCUCAUGCCUCAACCUCCCAAAGUGCUAAGAUUAUAGGCAUGACCACCAUGCCUGGCCUUUUCUGCUUUCUGAGGAGGAAAAAGGUACUGGUGGCAGAGAUCCAAAAGAAAAGUUGCCAGUGGCAGUGUGGAAAUUCACCUGAGAACAACAGGACAAGCUGGGGCACAAAUGCAAAGAUGCAGAGGGAGGCAACACCUGGUCAUCUGUGAGACCUUCAUGGGACCUGAAGACGCAGCACAGAGGAGGAACUUGAAAAAGGACGGGAUUUCUACUACUCAAGCAUUCCAGCCUAGGGUGAAUGUUUCCCCCUCCAAGAAGGGGCCCUUGCAGCACCACAACCUGCUUGUCUGCCACGUGACGGAUUUCUACCCAGGCAGCAUUCAAGUCCGAUGGUUCCUGAAUGGACAGGAGGAAACAGCUGGGGUCGUGUCCACCAACCUGAUCCGUAAUGGAGACUGGACCUUCCAGAUCCUGGUGAUGCUGGAAAUGACCCCCCAGCAGGGAGAUGUCUACACCUGCCAAGUGGAGCACACCAGCCUGGAUAGUCCUGUCACCGUGGAGUGGAAGGCACAGUCUGAUUCUGCCCGGAGUAAGACAUUGACGGGAGCUGGGGGCUUCGUGCUGGGGCUCAUCAUCUGUGGAGUGGGCAUCUUCAUGCACAGGAGGAGCAAGAAAGUUCAACGAGGAUCUGCAUAAACAGGGUUCCUGAGCUCACUGAAAAGACUAUUGUGCCUUAGGAAAAGCAUUUGCUGUGUUUCGUUAGCAUCUGGCUCCAGGACAGACCUUCAACUUCCAAAUUGGAUACUGCUGCCAAGAAGUUGCUCUGAAGUCAGUUUCUAUCAUUCUGCUCUUUGAUUCAAAGCACUGUUUCUCUCACUGGGCCUCCAACCAUGUUCCCUUCUUCUUAGCACCACAAAUAAUCAAAACCCAACAUGACUGUUUGUUUUCCUUUAAAAAUAUGCACCAAAUCAUCUCUCAUCACUUUUCUCUGAGGGUUUUAGUAGACAGUAGGAGUUAAUAAAGAAGUUCAUUUUGGUUUAAACAUAGGAAAGAAGAGAACCAUGAAAAUGGGGAUAUGUUAACUAUUGUAUAAUGGGGCCUGUUACACAUGACACUCUUCUGAAUUGACUGUAUUUCAGUGAGCUGCCCCCAAAUCAAGUUUAGUGCCCUCAUCCAUUUAUGUCUCAGACCACUAUUCUUAACUAUUCAAUGGUGAGCAGACUGCAAAUCUGCCUGAUAGGACCCAUAUUCCCACAGCACUAAUUCAACAUAUACCUUACUGAGAGCAUGUUUUAUCAUUACCAUUAAGAAGUUAAAUGAACAUCAGAAUUUAAAAUCAUAAAUAUAAUCUAAUACACUUUAACCAUUUUCUUUGUGUGCCAUCACAAAUACUCCUUAACCAAAUACGGCUUGGACUUUUGAAUGCAUCCAAUAGACGUCAUUUGUCGUCUAAGUCUGCAUUCAUCCACCAGCCUAGGCCUCCUGUCUUAAUUUUCAUACAGACAGAAAUGACUCCCCACUGGGGAAAGAGCAAAGCAAUACAUGUAGCACUCUUUUUCAAACACUGGUCUUUUUUUUUUUCUUAACAAUCCAACAUUGUUAUGUGUUUUGCGUCUCAUAUUGACACCUUUUGGUCAAGGUAGAGGACAUGUUUGUUGUAAGCUUUCUUUUUCGUGUAGAGGAUGGAUUCUUCACUCCUGAUACACACAAUCAGUGCACAGCAGCUCUCUUAUACAUCCAGUUGAUGCCUUCAGUCUCCCUGGCUUCUUACAAGCAUCUUCUGGGCCUUGUGUGUCCCUGGGCACCUGUCCCUGGUCAAUUCCCGAAAGCUACUGUGCUCCUCUUGCCCAUCUCCCCUUGCAAAUAAUAUCUUCCAUCGGGGGACCGGCUUCCUCCAAUUUCAGGAGAGGUGGGGCUGAAGGCACAGACUUGGGCGUCACUGGCACAGAUAUAAGUAAAUACAGCUGGAGUCUGCAGAGAGGCUGGACUGAGUCAGGGAGUCAGGAAAGAGAAGCCACACACAAGGACAACCAAUCAUGUUUCUCAUAAUCUUCUUAACCUAGGGAAUAGGACACAAUCAUUUUUUCUUUUUAAAACAUCUUUAUCCCUGAUCAGCCUCAUUUCCUCAAAAACUAUAAAGGAAAAUGCUGCUGACUUGUUUUUGCGUAGUAAUUUCAGCUGUCACAUAAUAAGCUAAGGAAGACAGUAUAUAGUAAAUAAGGACCCUUUAUCUGUCUUAUUUUCCCUUUUGGCUUCACAGGAAACUUGUGAGAAACCUAUGCAGCAUAAAAUUAAUAUGAUUUCAAUCCAGGGAUUCAACGAUGGAAGGAGGUCAUGAGAAUAGCAGAAAGUCUUCAAAUCGAGAUCAUUAUGAAAUCCUCAGACCCAGAGCACAUAAAUCCUACCCUCAGAGUCACUGAGCAGUUAACAUUACAAAUUACAAACCAUAUCCAGUCAGAGUCAUUCUCUUUCCUGCUUGUCUCCUGUACUCAUGUUACAGGUUAGGGCAGUACCCCGAGUGGAGUGAACAAUCUCUGGACUAACACUUGUCAGGAUCAGAAGCUGAGGUAUCUGCACCCACAUUACAGGAACAGGAUAUGUGCUCCUAGGGAACUGAGGGUGUCAGGAGAUGAGGAAUGUCCCUGGAGUCACAGAAAGAAGGUAUCAGAUGUGUCUCACUCUGACAUAUGCAGGUGUUUAUGAAACUCUGGGAUUUCUAAGGAAGGAUGCAGUGCAGAGACAGGUCCCAGAGGAGACAAGAGCUGAGAGACCAUCCAAACUGGGACCACCUUGUCACUAGACUUCAAAUUUUCAAUAUUGAUAGAGUGUUUUCUAAGAGUCAGGCCCUUUGCUGAGUGCUAUGUGCAGCAGGAUCAAAGGCAGCCAGGAGGUAGAGGAGUCUUGAGGUACAUCAGUCAUUGGAGUUGAAGAGCAGAGAUUCAAAGGAAAGUUGGAACUGGAGCUUUAAAGGAGAUGUGAAGUGGGUGACUCAACCUCUGACUCAGAAAAAUUGAUACCUGCAGAAGAAAAAACCCGGCGGGCUUAGGACUCCCAGCUGAGUGUUGUAUCCUCCAUCCCUUUCCACCUGGUCCCUUCAUUUUCUACCCCUCACAGUUCCCUAACGAGAAGGUGGUCCACCCAACAGACAACGCUGCCUCAGAUGGUUAUCAAGGGGUACCCUAAGAAGAAAUCAUCUCACCCUCUCUUUGUCCCCAUUUGUCAAGUAGCAGUGAGGCCGAGCCAGGGGAUGGUGAAAGUGGAAGGAGGUGGGAGUUGGGCAUCGGGUGUGAAGAUGCUCUUGAAAGGGGUUUUAAUAACCACUUGCUACCAGGCCAGUGAACACUUACCAUAGUUGAUGCCUUUUGAGCAUGUUGCAUUGUAAACUGUCCCUGAAAUUACUGUGCACUUGGCUUAUGGGAUGAAACAUCCUCCUAGUUCUUUUGUCUCUCAGCUUCUCUGAAGUCUCAUUGAGCACCUUCUCUUCAAUUUCUUUUACACAGUAAGAAUAGGAUCAGCUGUGCUAAACUAACAAAUACCCAGAUAUCCAGGUUUGGCUCAUGUUACACGUCCAAAGUAAGUCAUGCAGGAAGCUCUGCUCAUCAUCGUACUCAGGAAGCCAGGCUGACAGUCUUUCUCCUGCACAUCUGCUCCCAGAACCUCCCCAGCAGAAUGAAGGGAACCUAAGAAUUUAUUCACUGGCUUUUAAUGAUCCCUCCUAGAAAGAACACACUUCUCGCAUUUCAUUUUCCAAUGUAAAUCAUAUGGCUGCAACUAACUUCAAAUAAGUGGGAAUACUUGAAGGUGGAAAACAUUUAAGAAGUACACACUAAAUAAAUAAUAAAAUACUUCUACAAGAGA